AGAAGCUAAUUGACUAGGGAAGGAUCAGGAAGACAAGACACAUCAAAAAGGGGAGGGAAUCUACAAUGGAAGGACACAAGAAAGAUCAGCUGGAUUAAGUAGUCAUGAUUAUGCAAAGCCAUAUCCAGAGACCAAGGUGUAAAGCAGGUCGGAGAAAAUGGAAAUCUCAAGAUUGGCUCAGUCAAAAAGAAACAUUAUCAGUUUGAACAUGGACCUUGAAAGGGAUACGCAGAGAAUAGAUGAAGCAAAUCAGAAACUUCUUCUCAAAAUCCAAGAGAGGGAAGAUAAGAUUCAGAGGCUGGAAAGUGAGAUCAUUCAGACGCGGGGCCUGGUGGAAGAUGAAGAGUGGGAGAAGGAGAACCGCACCACGAUGGAAAGGGAAAGAGCCUUGCAGGAGCUGGAGGAAGAAACAGCCAGACUUGAAAGGAAGAAUAAGACGUUGGUCCACAGUAUAACAGAACUUCAACAAAAGCUUACAAGGAAAUCACAAAAGAUAACCAAUUGUGAACAAAGCAGUCCAGAUGGAGCCCUAGAAGAGACAAAGGUUAAGUUACAACAGCUGGAAGCUUCCUAUGCAUGCCAAGAGAAGGAGCUGCUCAAGGUAAUGAAGGAGUAUGCAUUUGUGACCCAGCUCUGUGAAGAUCAAGCCCUCUACAUAAAGAAGUACCAGGAAACGUUGAAGAAAAUAGAAGAAGAACUAGAGGCUCUGUUCCUUGAGAGAGAAGUAUCAAAACUCGUGAGCAUGAACCCUGUGGAAAAAGAGCAUACCAGCCAAAAUAAUGAGGGUACUCCUACCCAAAAGACAGCAAGAUUAUUCAGUAAAAAAUGGGCCUCCUCCUUUUAGUGGCAAGAUGGCUGCCAACAAUCCAGAUCUCGUACUACCAGAUUGGCAACCUUUGCAGAAUAAAAGUCUUUUCCAACAGGUUCAGCAGUAAAGUCCAGAAAAGGUCAUAAACUGGCCUAUCUGAGGUCAAUUGCCUACCCUGUCCCACAGUCAAUGUGGCCAGAGGGAUGGAGUACUCUGAUUGGUCAAGCUUAUGUCAUAUGUUCAGCCCCUUACUAAGGAUUAAGAGCAGUCAAAGAAGAAGAACAAAGUAAGGGAAUGACCUAAACUAUAUGAAAUGCAUUUCUCCCACUAAAAGGGGCUCAGUGCCUAUGGAAGAGAAAAGGGAUGCUGGACACGCAAAAGCAGAGGUCUACUUCAUUGCUAAACUCUGUGUCUUCCUAUAAGCAAAAAUUAUAACUUCUAAAGAUAGUAGAUUAAGACGGUGAAAGCUUCUACAAAGAGCUCAGUUUAAGAACCAUGUAAAUAAUCAGGUCACUAGGGCUAAAGUAAGCAACAAUUCUAAAAUAAGUAGAAUAUGACUGGUAUAAAUUGCUUCACCAACUCAAAGUAGCAUAUAUAUCACACCUCUUAUUUUUCCAAUUAAUUGCUGAAACAUUCACAUGCCUUACUAAUAGGAUAUACUCUACAUUAUUUUCCAGUACAAGAGAAAAUUAUUUUAAAUGGUAAGGUUUUAGGUCUAAAAGUGUCUCAAUUUUAAGAAAGCUGAUAUCAAGCAGGUCAUAUUUUCUAGGCAUUGUGCAAUGACUAUAGAAAUUAUGAAAAUGUGUAACCAACCAGUAAUAUCUAGCCACAGGCAAAUUUUAUAAAAGAUCCUUUUAAUUAACUUCUGGAUUAAAUGGAAAAUCCAAACUGAGAUUACUUUUAUAGGGUCAGUUACAUGCUAAGGAGGAAGCAUAGAGAGUAGAAGAAUGGUUACCAGAGGCUGUAACCUUCUUAAUUUAAGGUAAAAAAUUCUACCUAUUAGCUUAGUAUUAGAUGAAAACAGAAAUUCUUGUCACAUACAGGCACUAUUCACUGCAGUGAAGUAUAUCUUUUCAGAAAGUUGCAUAAAAUCGAAUAAAAUACCAUGUAUUAAAUUAAAAAAACUGGAUAUAUUUGAA